GCCAUACCUUAAGUCUGGACCAUUUAUCCCUGUAGGGAGUCCCUCUUCCCCUCUAUUCUCUUUCAGAACUACUUAUUACUUUAGGUUCAGUGUAUGUAGCAUAUGGUGACUUUAUGGGUUUCAGUUUUCUGAACCCCAAAUAUGCAAAAAUAUAGAAAAAGCAGACCAGGCAUCCCACCUUCUGUGUGUCACUAAGGGAGCAUCUCUUCCUCUUUCUCCCCUAAUAAGUUGUAUAUUAUUUUCUCAGUAUUUUAAUUUUUUGCUAUUUAUAUUAUCUGAGAUUUAUCAUUGGAAUCACACAAAUAUUAAACCAGGAAAGAUCACCCAGGAAGAAAUUGAGAUCACCCACAAUAUCAGUAUUUGAAGCUGAAGAGUCCUGAAGCUGCAGGAAAAAUGGAGGAAACCAACAACAGCUCUGAAAAGGGAUUUCUUCUCCUGGGAUUUUCAGAUCAGCCUCAGCUAGAGAGGUUUCUUUUUGCCAUCAUUUUGUACUUCUACGUCUUGAGCCUUCUGGGGAACACUGCCCUCAUACUAGUAUGUUGUCUGGACUCCAGACUCCACACUCCAAUGUACUUCUUCCUCAGCAACCUCUCGUGUGUGGACAUCUGCUUUACCACCAGUGUUGCCCCACAGUUGCUGGUUACCAUGAAUAAGAAAGACAAAACCAUGAGCUACGGUGGCUGUGUGGCCCAGCUCUACGUGGCCAUGGGGUUGGGCUCGUCUGAGUGUAUUCUCUUGGCCGUCAUGGCUUAUGACCGCUAUGCUGCUGUCUGCCGGCCACUGCGCUACAUAGCCAUUAUGCACCCCAGGUUCUGUGCGUCUCUGGCCGGUGGAGCAUGGCUCAGCGGCCUCAUCACCUCCCUAAUUCAGUGCUCCCUCACUGUGCAGCUGCCCCUCUGUGGUCAUCGCACACUGGAUCAUAUUUUCUGUGAGGUGCCAGUGCUCAUCAAACUGGCCUGUGUGGAUACGACUUUCAACGAGGCAGAACUCUUUGUGGCCAGUGUAGUCUUUCUAAUUGUCCCGGUGUUACUCAUCUUAGUCUCCUAUGGCUUUAUCACUCAAGCUGUGUUAAGGAUAAAAUCAGCUGCGGGCCGCCAAAAGGCCUUUGGGACCUGUUCGUCUCACCUGGUUGUGGUCAUCAUUUUCUAUGGGACCAUCAUAUUCAUGUACCUUCAACCGGCCAAUAGGAGAUCCAAAAACCAGGGAAAGUUUGUUUCUCUUUUCUAUACCAUAGUCACCCCACUUUUAAACCCCAUUAUCUACACUCUGAGAAACAAAGAUGUGAAAGGGGCCUUGAGGACCCUGAUACUGGGUAGUGCUGCUGGACAAAGCCACAAGGACUAGGAAACACCUGGAAUUCUAAACAAGGGAAACACCUCAAGGCAGAGUGAGGGUUCAUCCUCCCCAGACAUUCCUCUUGUCAAUCCCAAAGCCACAGGGACUAGGAAGCAUUGGAAUUCUAAAGAAGGGAAACACCUCAAGGCAGCGUGAGGAUUCAUCCUCCCCAGACAUUCCUCUUGUCAAUCCCAAAGCCACAGGGACUAGGAAGCAUUGGAAUUCUAAAGAAGAGAAACACACCAAAGCAGCAUGAGGGUUCAUCCUCCCAGACAUUCCUCUUGUCAAUCCAAGACCCUGUGUUCUAUCUGGAAAAAAAUGUUUGUCCUUCGUCCACCUGCCAUCAAGGUUCAUGUAUCCAUUAUUUCCUUCUAAUGUGCCAGCCCAUCUGAUAGACUUCUACUAAUGCUUCAAAACUCAGCUGAAAUGUCACCUGCACUCACUAGCUGUCCUGAAACACCAUCCUUCUCAUCCUUGUGCAGAAUUAACUGUUUCAUAAUAUGUUUCCAUAGCACUUGAUCCACACUACCAUUUCUACAUUUCACAUUUGAGAUAUAUGUAUACAUAUAUCUCUAACUAGGCAAAGCAAUGUAUAUAACAGACUGAAAAAAUACAUGACCAUUUUCCCAGAAUAUGUCACUUUUAACUGGAGAAUGGAACCAUCCCACUCUAUUGGCUUAUUUACAACACGAGAAACACAAAUAUUAAGAGUUGUGAUGCUUUGGUUCCACAGAAUUGUGGGAUGCAAAUAAUGACUAAUAUUUUAUUAAAGGAAUCAAAUAAGCAAACUUGAAUUAAGGAGAUUGAUUAAAAGUUGAGUAAAAUUGCCAUAUACUAAAAUGUGUUUUAACAUUUAUACAAAAUUCAUAAAAUAAGUUAUUGUUUUUGGCCUUAAACUCUGGAAAACAGUUACUUAUGUAAUUUUAUACUUCAAAAAUUUGAAAUAUGAAUCCCACACACUGUCUCACGUUAACGAUCAUAGUUAUAUGUUUGGUUUCCAAAACAGCAAAAAAAAUGAAAUAUUUAGAAGCAUUUUAAUAAAUGUAUUCUUAUAUUUGACCAAACUUUUACUUUCUGAUUUAAUUCUCUGUCUCUAUCUCUCUGUGUAUCUUUGUGUGUCUCAGCCUCUUUCUUGCUUUCUUUUCCCAAAACGAUUGAACUUCAUCAAUUCGUCAACCUCAAGUAUUUUAAGAGAACUGUGCAAUUAUAGAAAAAAGUGAUUUAAUCUGUGGUUGUAAUUUUACUUCAUAUUCUCAUUAUGAUACACAUGAAAAAAGCAUGAAAACAUCAAUGCAAAUGAAGAGUAAAAUGCAGGCAGAAUCUGGGGUGGAAGUGGAAUUUUCAAGUGAUUUAGACUUUUCUUUUUUGGACAGGGUCUUGCUCUGUUGCCCAGGCUGGAGUGCAGUGGCUCAAUCAUGGCUCACUGCAGCCUUGACCUCCUGGGUUUAAGUGAUCCCUCUGCCUCAGCCUUCCAACAUUCAGAUUUAUAAUAAUUCAUCCUGGUGUGAGAAUAUUGUAGCCUGUCUACGAAUGUUAAGGAUAACGUUUGGACCUGCCUCUCCUACCAAAGCCUGGACUGAAGGCAAAAUGGCUGCGCACACAAGAACAAAAAGGCAUCAGGAGAAUUCACUAAUGACUCAGGCUGCCUCUUCACAAAUACCCUGUCCAGCUGGCACCUCUUCAAUAUACUUUUAGCAAACAAAAUGAUGAAUAUCCAAUUUAACAAAAACGAGGGAAAAGAAGCCUGGUUAAAUUUGUCUUCUAGGAUAUUCUUAUGUGAUUUUCCUCCUCCAGUAAUGGAGAGGAGAGUUUGGAACUGAGCAGAACAUGCUGAGGAGCACAUGUUUUUAUUUACAAUAUGCAAGUAGAGAAGUAGUUCUACAGGAAGCGUCACAUGUACAAAUGCAUUAUUCCUGAUAACCCGAGCAACACAGCAUAGGAAAGAAUGUACCUGUGUCAGAGUCUCAAUCAAUUUACAUGGAAUAUGGCCCCAGGGCAAAAGAUGUGGCAUUUAAAGGAAAGAAAUAGCUCCAGGUGAAAAGACAACCAUGUGUAAAGCAAUGAUAUGAACACAAUAUGUAGAAAAACCUACAUAUGAAUUGUGAAGCAACCAUUUUCAAAGACAAACUCACAUCCAUUUAAGGUAAUAUGGAAUACAAAUCCCACUGAAAAUAAAAUCAAAUUAUUACUGUAUACAAUAAAUUCAAACAUAAUUCAGAAAAAAAUAGAAUAUCUGCUUAUUGCUGAAAUUAGCAUCUUUAGCUGUAAGUUAUUUGCACCCAAAAGGAAACCAGAAAAUAAUAGAUAUAACAUAGGCAAAGCAACCUAAAAAAACUACUUAACUGCAGAUGAAAAUGGGAACACAUUUGAAAAUAAAAUCCUGUUACUACUUUCUUGAAUUUAGAGCUUUCCUAUGAUAUGGAUAUGUUUAUACUGCUUUUAUAAUCAUCAUACAUGUAUAAUUUCAUACUAUUUUUAUUUAUAAUGUGAGCAUUUUUCUGAUUAAUCUAAAAAAUAUCCACCAUUUAUUAAAAAUCUUCCCUAUAAUUGAAUAACAUGAGUAGUUUCUCUUUUUUAAAUACCUACAUUGAGCAUACUUUUGUUUGUGAAUGCUUAUAAUUAUGUACUUAUAAUGUAUUUUAUAAAUACAAUUAGUAAAUCUAAAACAGGUACACAUCAGUCAAUUUGCACACAUUACUAGCUUGAUCUGCAGAACACGUUUUCAAAGGAUGCGCCAAGAAAAAAACUAUCACUUAGUUAAAUGACCAUUCAGUAUUGCAAUUAUUUAAAAACUAUACAAUGAGAAUGCUGUAAUAAGUAUAUGGUUCCACCACUCCAAACACCAUGAAUUUUUUUUAAAAGAUAUUUUUAAGAAAAAAUAAAAUGAUUUUACAUAACAAAUAUUAAUGAAUUCAUGAAAAACAAAAACCAUAUAGGACCACAGCUCAGAGAAGAAAAAUGGGAGGCACUUACUAUUUAAACCCUAACCCAAAUGGUCAGUAAAAAGACAAGUACCAGCUACUACAAAAAAACACCAAAAUAUAAAGACCAAUGAUACUGUGAAGAAACUGCAUUACCUAAUGUGCAAAAUAACCAGCUAGCAUCACGAUGACAAGAUCAAAUUCACACAUAAAAAUAUUAAUCUUAGGCAGGGCACAGUGGCUCACACUUGUAAUCAUAGCACUUUGGGAGGCUGAGUCAGGUGGAUCAUGAGGUCAGGAGUUCAAGCUCAGCCUGGCCAGCAUGGUGAAACCCCAUGUCUCCUAAAAAAAAUACAAAAAAUUAGCCAGGCACAGUGGUGCAUGCCUAUAAUCCCAGUUACUCAGGAGGCUGAGGCAGAAGAAUUGCUUGAACCUAGGAGGCAGAGGUUGCAGUGAGCCAAGAUCGUGCCACUGUACUCCAGCCUGGGCAACAGAGCAAGACUCCAUCUCAAAAAAAAAAAGAAAAAAAUGUAUAUGUUAUCACUUUGGUCUCAUUUGAGUAUGAAUGAUCAGACAGGGAAAAUAAAAGUACCAAGAAAAAUAAACAAGGGUCUUAUAAUAAAAGCAACACAGAAUGGCCAAAGCUAUCCUGAGCAAAAAGAGGAAAAAAGCUGGAGCCAUCACAUUACUAGACUUCAAAAUAUACUACCAAGUUAUAGUUACCAAAACAGCCUGGUAUUGGCAUAAAAACAGACACAUGGGCCAAUAGAACAGAAUGGAGAACCUAGAAAUAGAUUCAUGUAUUUACAGCCAACUGAUUUUUGACAAAGGUGCCAAGAACAUACACUGGGGAAAGGAGAGUUUCUUCAAUAAAUGUCCUGGAACAGUAAUCAGCAGCUGGGGCUGGUACCAUAGGGAUACUUAAAGUUGAAUUUAUCAAUUGCUGGAAGCUCAUGUGAACUAACUUGACAAAUAAAAACAAUGUUGAGCCCCAGUCUUAGGAAAUCCUCCCUAUACUCAUGAUUUUUACCUUCAGGAGUCUCAACAGCUUCUCACUGUGCAAAGUAGAGAGAAAUUCCCUUUUGCUUUGGCAGAGAGAGGAGAAAAUAAACAUUUGAAAUAUGCCCAGAGCUCUCUGUUCACCAUAACCUGAUCUCAGUAGUAACUAUUUAAUGAUUGCCAUUCUAACUGGUGUGAGAUGAUAUCUAUUGUGGUUUUGAUUUGCAUUUCUCUGAUGGCCAGUGAUAAUGAGCAUUUUUUCAUGUGGCUGUGGGCUGCAUAAAUAUCUUUUGAGAAGUGUCUGUUCAUAUCUUUCGCCCACUUUUUGAUGGGUUUUUUUUUUCUUAUAAAUUUGUUUGAGUUCUUUGUAGAUUCUGGAUAUUAUCCCUUUGUCAGAUGAGUAGACUGCAAAAAUUUUCUCCCAUUCUCUAGGUUGCCUGUACACUCUGAUGGUAGUUUCUUUUGCUGUGCAGAAGCUCUUUAGUUUAAUUAGAUCCCAUUUGUCAAUUUUGGCUUUUGUUGCCAUUGCUUUUGGUGUUUUAGACAUGAAGUCCUUAUCCAUGCCUAUGUCCUGAAUGGAAUUGCCUAGGUUUUCUUCUAGGGUUUUUAUGGUUUUAGGUCUAACAUUUACGUCUUUAAUCCAUCUUGAAUUAAUUUUUGUAUAAGGUGUAAGGAAGGGAUCCAGUUUCAGCUUUCUACAUAUGGCUAGUCAGUUUUCCCAGCACCAUUUGUUAAAUAGGGAAUCCUUUCCCUAUUUCUUGUUUUGUCAGGUUUGUCAAAGAUCAGAUAGUUGAAGAUGUGUGGUAUUAUUUCGGAGGGUUCUGUUCUGUU